GGGGCGGUAGCCGAGCCUGUGGCCCGGGCGGGGCUCCUCUCCGGCGGCGCCGGAGUCUGGGGGCCGCGGCUUCCCCCUCCCGGCCAGCGGCGGCUCCUGGCCCCUCCUCCCCCGGCCGCCCCCAUCCCCGCCGCCGCCGCCGCCAAAGCUAAACCCGGCCGUUGCCUGCAGGAGCCGCGGCAGCGGGCGAUCGGGCCGUGAGGAGCCUCGGGCGCGGCCUCGCCUCCCGGGCCCGGCGCCUGCCUCAGCACAGCGGACAGCGCCGCGCCCCUUGCCUGGACCCAGCCGCCCGCCCGCCCCCGGCCCACCUGAGCCCGGGCCCGCGGCGCCCGCAUCAGCACUGCGGACAGCGCCCCGGGCCCCAGCUCGCCGCCACCGCCGCCGCCCACCUGCUCCCGGGGUCAGCACCGCGGAGACCCCCCUCGCCCGGCCCCGCGACAGCCUCCGAGCGCCCCCGGAUCAUGGCCACCGAGGUCCACAAUCUGCAGGAGCUCCGGCGAAGUGCCUCACUGGCCACCAAGGUCUUUAUCCAGAGAGACUACAGCGAUGGGACCAUCUGUCAGUUCCAGACCAAAUUCCCCCCAGAGCUGGACAGCCGGAUCGAGCGGCAGCUCUUUGAAGAGACUGUGAAGACCCUCAACGGAUUUUACGCAGAGGCUGAGAAGAUUGGGGGCAGCUCCUACCUCGAGGGCUGCCUGGCCUGCGCCACGGCCUACUUCAUCUUCCUCUGCAUGGAGACCCACUAUGAGAAGGUUCUCAAGAAGAUUUCCCGCUACAUCCAGGAGCAGAAUGAGAAGAUCUUUGCACCUCGAGGCCUCCUACUUACAGACCCUGUGGAGCGUGGGAUGAGGGUUAUUGAGAUCUCCAUCUACGAGGACCGGUGCAGCAGUGGCAGCUCCAGCAGCGGCAGCAGCAGCGGCAGUGGCAGCAGCAGCGGUGGGGGUGGUGGGGCGGGGGCCCGGUGACUGGCCGAGAGUCCCUGUAGGGAGGUGUAUGGCCGGAGUGAGGGCCUUGCAGACCUGCGGCGGCUGCGCUACCAGAGCACCCGCUUCUGAGUCAUUCUUUGGGCUCACCCUGCUGCCCGGGGUGGGAGGGAGGGUGACGGGCCUCAUAUUUCCUGUGGGCCAUCAACCUAUGCCCCCUGUCCCUCACCCCCGUCUGGAUCAGUCCAUUUCCUGACCUGGGGGCUUUUCCUUCCCGAUGGGGCUGGUCUGGGCCACACAGAGACAGAUCUUCCUAGGAAGGCUGGGGUGGGGAGAACACAACCUAGGCGGCCCCUCUCUUCCACAGCCCCUCUCCCAACCCUGCGAGGGGGGCCGAGGCCUGCCACAUAGAGGACUCCCACACUGCAUGACCCCUCAUCCCAAACCCAUAUCCACCAGGACUCUUUCCCUUGGGCCCUGCGUCCCGUGGCUGUCUCCCAGUAUCUGUUCCUUCUCAUGCCCCUGCAGGGCCCCGGCCUGUCUAUGAUCCUGCCUCCACCAAAUUCAAGGUGUGGGGAGACGGGUGCCGUGGUUGGGAGCUGUUCAGCGCACUCCUGACCUCUUCUAGACCUAUGGCUUUCCUGUCCUGCAUUCAGAGCUAGAGGCCAGCUCGGCCUUGCGAGAAGCAUCCAACUUUGAGACUUUGCAGGCUGCCAGGUGCUGGUUGGGGGGCACAGAGCCUGGGGCUCUGGGAGGUAAUAUGGGGGUCUGGGAAACUCCGUGAAGAGACAUAGCCAUGCGGGGCCUGAAUCUCCUGAACUACAGCCAGUUUCCUGAGAUUAGAACCUGUGUGUAUGCACAUGUGAAUGUAUGUGUGAGUGCACAUGUGUGUAAGUGCAGUGUGCGUAAAUGUGUGAGUCUGCGUGUGUUAGCAUGCCUGUAUGUGAGCGCGUGUGUGAGCGCAUGUGUGUGCACCAGUGCACAAGUGUAUGAAUGUGGACACAUUUAUAAGCACACCUGUGUGUGUCUGAGUACAUGUGCACACACGUGUGCACAAAUGUGCAUUUAUAUGAGUGUGAGUGCAUGCAUGUGCAUGAACAUGUGUGCACAAGCAUGUGUGUAUGAGUGUUCAUGUGUAUGAGUGUGUGUGUAUGCAGGUGAGUGCAUGUGUGUGUGAGUGUGUUUGUGUGUUCCCCUUGGCUGCCAGGCCAACGACUGCUUCUCUGCAUCCUGCUGUCUUCGCUACCUGAGGGUCUGUGACUUCUUCCCUGUGUGGGUCCAGCCUGACCCCCUGUAAGUAAAUGUCCAAAAGCCCCUUGCCCCUCCCCUAGGGCUACCAGGGAACAUACUCUACUGCAUAUGUUCUAGUGGAAGAGAAGCCGGGGUUCUAGGAAAGAAGAGCCAAACUUUGGUGGCCUUUGGUGCCCCCUCUCAGCUCCCCAUGACAAGACAACGGGGCUGCAGACACUGUGUGUUCAGCCUGCCCAGGGGCUGGGGCUCUUUAAGGCUUUGUAGGUGAGGUUUCCAUGGACCUUCAAAGGUGCCAGCAGCCUGCAGGGGAAAGGCAAACUCCCUCCUUGCAAGGAAAGGAGAUGUCCAGCCAAUGAUGCCCGGCUUCUGAGGCCCAGAGGAGCAGGUGGGAUGGGAGCAGCCCCUGGGGCUGGUGUCCCGAAGAUGAAAUGAAGGGGGCUGCCUAUCUCAGUUGGCGGGAGGUGUUAGAAGUGGAUGUGCAAGACCAGCCACUGGAGGUAGCUCUCUGGAGUCAAAGAGAGGCCUGCUUUUCUACCAGACAUGGGAGCAGCAUGUAGGAUACAAGGGCCUACCCAGAGACCAGAGAGAGUCAGCCUAGUCCUUGCAGCCUCAGGAAGUCCUCGGCCCAAGUGAGUCCUGGUCCAAGGAUCCCCCUGGAGAGCCGCAGUUCAGUGGGCUCCACCGCAGCCCCUGGCCACGGCCUAUGCCCUCCCUGGGCCCCUGUGGGGCUGGGCAUUGUGUCUGACCUGUGCAUCUCCCAUGGGAGGGCUGGGCACAGGCAGUGCUAUGGCCUUUUUUUUUUUUUUCUUUUUCCAAUAAAAGAACUUGCCCAGCGUGAAGCUCUGUGAUGCUUUCUCUGCCCCGUGACGAUGGAGGGUCAGUUCUAUGCUCCAGGACCACAUGAGGGGAUACUCAGCUGCCUGAACUGGACCUGACAUGGGGAGCAGGAUGAACUCUGUCUUCUUGGAGCUUGCAGUCUACUGAAGAGGCAGACACCUCAGCAUCUCUAAUCUGGAAUCUUUGGGGCACUUGUAGCCUUGGGUGGGGGAACAGGUUGGACUGAAAGCGAGGCCAAAAGUAAUCAAUUAAUGAUAUCAAUAAAUCCUCAUUUCUUGAGCUCUUCCCCUGGGUUGGGUCCUGUUGGGAGCUGGAUCACACAGGUCACUCAGUACUGAAGAUGAGAAAGUAGCUGGAUGAUCACUUCUCGGCCUUUUGGCCAAGAUCAAAUAUGGAGAAAGUAGCUGGAUGUUGGAACCUAGCAGAGUUGUGUCUUGAAUUUUAUAAUUUAUUGAGCACCUACUAUGUGCCAGAUACUUUGCUGAAACCAUAUGUUAGAGCUGGCAGGGGAUUUAAAGAUCACUUGAAUCCUGUCACAGAGGUCCAGAGAGGGUGGGUGACUUGCCCUAGGCCACACAGCUGGUUGAUGAUAACAGGGCCCAAGCUUGGAACCCAGGUCUCCUGACUCAGUGCCCACUCUGUUACCACAGGGAUGGCACCCAGAUGGGAAGCUGCCUGAGGCUGCAGGGAGGCUGGGAUCACAAACUCAGGCCUGUUCCCAGAGAGGGGCUCAUCAGACUGUGGGGACAACGGCUCCAGCCUCUUAGGUGGGGGCUGGGCAGUCCCCUCUGGGUGGUUCUCAUGUUUGUUGUCACUGCCGCUAAGGGCUGCAGUGAGCUGUGUGCAGCCUGGACUCACUCCCUCUGCUGGAACCUGGGCCGUGUGUGGGUUGCCACAAGUGAGCGUGUUCUCUAAUAUGAGGGCAGGUUCAUUCUGUUUUGGGAUAGGAAGUUUGUUCUACCCCGAGGCCAGAUUUGAAUCCAAACUCAGCUCUUCUAGAGAUGAGGUCCUGGGGAGGGGGUGAGGAUUUACUAAACGGGUAAAACCAAAUCUGGGUGCUUAUCUGACUGAGAGGCAUUCAACCCUUCCAUUUUCAAAUGGUAAUCAUAAUAAUAAUAGUAGCUGACGUUUAUUUAGCACUUCCUAUGUGCCAGGCACUAGGCUAAGACUCUACAUAAUUAGUCAUUCAAUUCUCACAGCAACCCUCUAUGGCAUGGAUUCUUAUUUCCCAUUUUACAUAUGGGGAAACUGAGGCUCAUGGACGUUAAGUAACUGGGAAAUUGCAGAUCUUGGCUUUGAAUCUAGGCAAUCUGACUCCAAACUGCAAGGAAGAAGACAGAUCCAGCCUCAGAGGCCGCUUAACAGCUUGAGGGCCUCAGCCGUCCUGGGAUUAGGAUCAGGCAGAUUCCCAGGGAAGGACUUGGAGCCAUGCCUGGGUUUUGAGGCCGGGCUGGCACCUCCACUUCCAGGGCAUCACGGGAGGGUGCAUGGGCUGUGCUCGCAGGCAUGCGGGACCCAGAGGCAGCCCGGUGAAGGGUAGUGGGGGACUCGACUCACUGUGGGCCUGGGGAGGUGUGGUUUCUCUCUGCUGGCUUAGUUACAGGUGGUGGCCUGUCUCUCCGGGGUCUGGCUGUAGCCAUGUCCCUGCACCCACCUUGCCAGCCAGGGACAGGCCCCAUCAAGACCCAGGAGCAGCUCCAGCCUCAGCCAGACUGUCCCCGAGGUCCCAAGUGAGGCCCCAGCCACUCAGGCAUGCCUCAGGAAGCUCCUGCUGCACAUGCUCCUCUCCCUGCGCCAGCACCCUGCUGUCUGGCUUCCUUCCUUUGGCCACAGGGCGGGUGUGUGUGAAACCACAGGGUUUACAGAAGCUCGAGGUGCCACUGAGUGGCAGGAUUAUGCACUGCACUCGGGGAAUCAAAGGUGGAGACAGAAAGAACUAUGGCUGUUGUGACACGUCCCCCACGGCUCCCCGGUUGGCAGCCACUGCCACCCGCAGGGACUUUUCUGUGGCUUCCAGAGGUGUGGGGCAAAGGUGGAGUCUGGUGACUUUCUCCCUAGGGCCAGCCCCUGGGCUGUCGAGCCUGGGAAACUCCACAUCCCUCUCCACACCUCUAGAAGGACUCACAAUGAGGGGGGCCCAGACAGGAGGCAUCACCACCUGGUUUGGGCUUUACCAUUCACCCAGGGAUAAGGCAAGGCAAACACCACUCCACAUCAGAUCUGAAUUUGAGCUCUGGCUUCAUGACACUGACACAUGAAGACUCUUGGAGCCUCAGAUUCCCCAGUUGUUAAAUAGGGAGACUAAUAUCUCACAGAGUUGUUUAGACCCGAGGCGUUCAACCUUGGUGGCAAUGGAUGUCAACUGGAAGCAUGAAAAAUCACCAAUGCCUGAUCCUAUCCUCAGAGAUUCUGAUUUAAUUGUUUUGGGGGACAGCUUGGGCAUCAGGAUUUUAAAGAGUUUCCCUGGUGAUUUUAAUGUGAAGGUAAGGCUGAGAAUCCCUGGUUUUGACAGUACCUAUAGCCUAUAAGCCUUUAAUACACCUCUGAAAAUGCCUGAGACCUGAAUAAGAAGUUUAUGGUUCCACAGAAGCAGCCAGACACAAAAAUGCAUAUGCACCAUGUGAUUCCCCUUAUAUGAAACUGAAAGACAGGCCAAACUCGCCUUUGAUUGGGAGUCAGGAUCAAGAUUACCCUGGGUCGGGGGUAGCGAAUGGAUGGGGACCUGGGGGGCUUCUGGGAGCUCAGGAUGUUCUGUUUCUUGAUCAGAGUGCCAGUUACACGGGGUGCUCACUUCAUGAGAAUUCACUGAGCUGUAUACUUAAGAGCUGUGUAUUUGUCUGUACUGGUGAUAUAUUUCAAUAAAAUUCACCAGAAAAGCCUGUUGGCUACAAAAUAGGAAAAGAAAGGACACACUUGAAAUUAACGUUUUGUUAAAUAUCUGGAAAUGUAACACAUAUGCCAAACAGACAACUGCAACUCUAUGUUACGUGUGUGUGUGUGUGUGUGUGUGAAAAUGUAAUGUCUGCUCUGCUGUGGGUGGGCCCUCUAAAAGGGAAGGUCCCUGAUGCCUAAGAAAAUCUGAAAACAGCCCAGGUUCACACCAGGAGUUCUUAACCUCGACCCGACUGCAUUCAGGUGCAUAUUAUGUGCCGUUAUCUGAGGAGAGCAUCUACAGCUUUCAGCAGAUUCUCAAAGGGGUAUGCAACCCCCUAAAAAGGUUAAGAACAAUUGGUUUUGAGGAGUCAGUAAGAAACUGGCCAUGAAUGUGCUUGGCAUGAAAGAGAUGCUUGGUAAUGUCGGUUUCUUUCCUUCCUUUCAGAGCCCAGCCUUCGGAGGUUUCCGCAUGAGCCUUCUCGGGCGACUUCUAGGAGGAUUUAUUCCCCUGGCAGUGCCAAGGGCAGCCUGCACCAAGCUCACAACUCUUCCUCCAAGAGGAUGUUCAAAGGGCCUGUCAUUUCAGCAUCUGCUGGACAGCAGAACUUCGCAUGCAGGAUCCUGGAGCUGCGUCGGGUUUUGAAUCAGGGACAAUGGAGGAAGUGGGAAACUGUGAAGAGAGUCAGAGGGCUGUGCCAGCUGCCCCCUUUCCCACCCCCAGCAAUUCACUUAACUUUCCUGAGUCUCACCUUUGUCAUUAUGAGAAUGUGUAUAUUUAUAAAUAAUCAUCUGUUUCUCCAAUGUAAGAUAUUGUUAUUGCAGAAGUGAUACUAGGACCUCGUUAUACGAUGGCCUCAUGAUGUAGAUUUAUAGCAGGCUUCAGAUUCUGGCAUAGAAUAAACAGAUAUUUAUCCAAGGGUUCACUGAUUCCCGAAUAAAUGCCAGGAACAUUCAUGUA